UUCCUUGGGGCCAGGGACCCCAGUGGGGCCGGUACAUCUCCCCGCCCCGGCCUCUGCACCCUGGAGGGACGGCAGGAGGGCUCUCUGUGCAGUUUGAGAGAACACCCAUACGCAGGAAAUGACCCCAACGCCACCGAGAGGGCGCCUGGAAUGGUACCAUGUCAACAAUUUGGGUCAACUAAAAUCAGCGUGUCCGCACCAUUUUCGCCCGCCCAAUUUCACGCGAUCCUGCGAAAGAAUGACCCAGACCGGUCCGGGCGCGGUGGCUCGCGCCUGUAAUCCCAGCACUUUGGGAGGCCGAGGCGGCAGAUCACAAGGUCAGGAGUUCGAGAUUGGCCUGGCCAACAUAGUGAAACCCCGUCUCUACUAAAAAUACAAAAAUUAGCCGGGCGUGAUGGCGGCCGCCUGUAAUCCCAGCUACUCGGGAAGCUUGAGACAGAAGAAUCGUUUGAAUCCGAGAGGCGGAGGUUGCAGUGAGCCGGGAUCGCGCCAUUGCACUCCAGCUCGGGCGGCAGUGCGAGACUCCGUCUCAAAAAGGAAUGACCCGGGUCGCAUGGGGUGAAGGGUCGGGAAGCGCCCCAAAAGGAGAACGGGGCUGGGCUCCGGGAUCCGUCGGCGAGGAAGGGGCGAAGGGGUGGAGGGACUCGGGCCAGGCCGCCGGGGAUGUCUGUGGUUACCUCCAAGCUCUGGAGGCCUUGGCGAGACCCGCGCCAUCCGCAGCUUGGUUCCUGCGACCUCAGCCGCAGGGCGGUCCGGCUCCGGUUUCCCAGCAACCAGGCGUCAUCCUUCCCAGCAAGCACUGCGUCCAACCCGCGACGUCGGACCACAAGGCCCAGCAUGCCCCGCGCGGACUACAAGCCCCACAAUGCACCGCACACCCUUUACUGGCCGGCCCCGCGCUGCUCUCCUAAGACCCCGCGGGCCAGCGCCGCGACCCCUUCCCAGCGCUCCUCGCGCUGUGUGCGGCGCGUCCUCUCGCCGGUGACCCGGUGUGCGUGGGGUCGAGGCGCCGGGCGGAGUGGCUCCGGGCCGAAACGCCAUGCGGAGGGGCGAGCGCAGGGACGCCGGAGGUCCGCGGCCCGAGUCCCCGGUGCCCGCGGGCAGGGCCUCGCUGGAGGAGCCGCCUGACGGGCCGUCUGCCGGCCAAGCCACCGGGCCGGGCGAGGGCCGCCGCAGCACCGAGUCCGAGGUCUACGACGACGGCACCAACACCUUCUUCUGGCGAGCCCACACCUUAACCGUGCUCUUCAUCCUCACCUGUACGCUUGGCUAUGUGACGCUGCUGGAGGAAACACCUCAGGACACGGCCUACAACACCAAGAGAGGUAUUGUGGCCAGUAUUUUGGUUUUCUUAUGUUUUGGAGUCACACAAGCUAAAGACGGGCCAUUUUCCAGACCUCAUCCAGCUUACUGGAGGUUUUGGCUCUGCGUGAGUGUGGUCUACGAGCUGUUUCUCAUCUUUAUACUCUUCCAGUUGCCACCACUAACUGUAGCCCCGCUGACGGGGGCACUGGCCUUGCAGACUGUCCAGGACGGCCGGCAGUUUCUAAAGUAUGUUGACCCCAAGCUGGGAGUCCCACUGCCAGAGAGAGACUACGGGGGAAACUGCCUCAUCUACGACCCAGACAAUGAGACUGACCCCUUUCACAACAUCUGGGACAAGUUGGAUGGCUUUGUUCCCGCGCACUUUCUUGGCUGGUACCUGAAGACCCUGAUGAUCCGAGACUGGUGGAUGUGCAUGAUCAUCAGCGUGAUGUUCGAGUUCCUGGAGUACAGCCUGGAGCACCAGCUGCCCAACUUCAGCGAGUGCUGGUGGGAUCACUGGAUCAUGGACGUGCUCGUCUGCAACGGGCUGGGCAUCUACUGCGGCAUGAAGACCCUUGAGUGGCUGUCCCUGAAGACGUACAAGUGGCAGGGCCUCUGGAACAUUCCGACCUACAAGGGCAAGAUGAAGAGGAUCGCCUUCCAGUUCACGCCGUACAGCUGGGUUCGCUUCGAGUGGAAGCCGGCCUCCAGCCUGCGUCGCUGGCUGGCCGUGUGCGGCAUCAUCCUGGUGUUCCUGUUGGCAGAACUGAACACGUUCUACCUGAAGUUUGUGCUGUGGAUGCCCCCGGAGCACUACCUGGUCCUCCUGCGGCUCGUCUUCUUCGUGAACGUGGGUGGCGUGGCCAUGCGUGAGAUCUACGACUUCAUGGAUGACCCGAAGCCCCACAAGAAGCUGGGCCCGCAGGCCUGGCUGGUGGCGGCCAUCACGGCCACGGAGCUGCUCAUCGUGGUGAAGUACGACCCCCACACGCUCACCCUGUCCCUGCCCUUCUACAUCUCCCAGUGCUGGACCCUCGGCUCCGUCCUGGCGCUCACCUGGACCGUCUGGCGCUUCUUCCUGCGGGACAUCACAUUGAGGUACAAGGAGACCCGGUGGCAGAAGUGGCAGAACAAGGAUGACCAGGGCAGCACCGUCGGCAACGGGGACCAGCACCCACUGGGGCUGGACGAAGACCUGCUGGGGCCUGGGGUGGCCGAGGGCGAGGGAGCACCAACUCCAAACUGACCUGGGCCGUGGCUGCCUCGUGAGCCUCCCAGAGCCCAGGCCUCCGUGGCCUCCUCCUGUGUGAGUCCCACCAGGAGCCACGUGCCCGGCCUUGCCCUCAAGGUUUUUUGCUUUUCUCCUGUGCACCUGGCGAGGCUGAAGGCGAGGGGUGGAGGAGGCCCCAGCACAGCCUCAUCUCCAUGUGUACACGUGUGUACGUGUGUAUGCGUGUGUGUACGCGUGUGUACGCGCGUGUGUACACAUGCGUGGCCGCCUGUGGUGUGCACGUGUGCUCUGGGCUCCGAGGCUUCUCCAGAGCUGGGAGCUGGCUGGCGUGGCAAGGGCAUGCUCUGGGGCAGUGUGUCCCUCAGGAACCAGGGUCCUCCCUCCCCUUUCUGCCUGGUCAGCCCCGUGGCCUCUGGCCCACCAAGCUCCCUGUCACCCAGCCAUGGUGUGGUCCAGGCAGGGACAUCUCGGUACCCUUUCUGCACUCCGUGGGCCCUGGGUGCGCUGAGGCCUGGAGGCGUCUACACUGGCUCCACAUCCACUUCCCCCGCAGCUCGUGUGGGCGCUCGUCCACAAACACUCCGUGGCUGAGAGGCAGCGGAUCCAGGCAGCGAUGCUGAGCCACCUCCUCCGAGCCUUCCUUUCACACAGACCACCCCGGAGGACACGUGGAUGAUGGGGUCAGAGAUCACUGAGCUGCCCCUCAAGGGGGCCUGGAACCCGGGUGCUGGGGUCAUGCUGCCUCCGUGGCUCCAAGGUGAGGGUCAUCUUCACGAGCAAAGAGAACCAAUAAAGUGACAACGAACGUCUGAGGCUUCCAGCCCUCCCCCCA